AGUCCUCCUCUCUCUCUUCAUGCUUUUUAGUCCUUUAACUUUCUCAGGAUCCUCAGGUUUAGUAGAGAAAUAAUCCCCUUUCUCCUUACGCACAAGAACAUUUUCAAGGGUGAAAUGGGGCAGUUGUUAGCUAUCACUAAAGAAACACAAAAGGAGACAAGUGACAAGAUUGCUGGAUGGGUUUUGUUGAAGUACUCUUAUUUAAGUAGUAUUGUCAUCAUUAUUAAAUUAAAGCCAACAUUUAUUUAGCUCUUACUAUUUGCUGGACGCUGUGCUGUGUGCUUUUAGACUGAUCAAUUGCAGAUUUGCAGGGUCAUAUUAAACUGCUUGGGACUGUCAAGAGAACAUCUGUUACAAUCUUUUUUCUGAUUUAGAAGUUUUAAAAAUUAAACUGUUUCAAACUUAAAAUGUAAAUAACUGCCAUGUUUCCAACAUGUGUAGUGGAAAAAAAUGGUUAGUAUAUGCAGAAUUUUGCAAACCAUUAAGAAAUAAAUGUCCCAAUAGAUAAACGAGCAAAUUACAUAGACAGGUAAUUGACAAAGUCCAAAUAACCAGUGAGUAAUCAAAGAAAUACAAAUUGAAAUGAAUCACCAUCAAACAAAAAAAAAGGGAUGGCAUUUUGUUACUCAUGAAAUUGGCAAAUUUUUUUUUAAAUGAUAAUAUCCAGUGAUGGUAAGGUUGUGGGAAAACAAGAAAUUUCAUAGGAUACUUUGGUAAGUUGAUAUGACUUUCUGGAGGGCAAUUUGUCAGUGCAGAUGAAAAGUCUUCCCAUUUUAAAGAUGGGAAACUUAAGGCCUAAGAAUCUAAGUGACUUGCUUAAAGUUACAAAGUCAUGGCUGGGCGCAGUGGCUCACACCUGUAAUCCCAACACUUUGGGGGGCCGAGGAGGGCAGAUCAUGAGGUCAGGAGUUCGAGACCAUCCUGGCCAACAUGGUGAAACUCCGUCUCUACUAAAAAUACAAAAAUUAGCUGGGCAUGGUGGUGUGCGCCUGUAGUCCCAGGUACUCAGGAGGCUGAGGCAGGAGAAUUGCUUGAACCUGGGAGGCAGAGGUUGCAGUGAUCUGAGAUCAUGCCACUGCACUCCAGCUUGGCGGCAGAGUGAAACUCUGUCUCAAAAAAAAAAAAAAAAGUUACAAAAUCACAGAGCAGUAAGGGACCAAGCCAAGACUAGGACUAAGCCAUCUGAUUCUAGCCCUCAAUCCACUGUCACUUAUAGCAAUGUUUAUAAUAGCGAUGUAUUGGAAAACAACCUAAAUGUCCUCAAUAUAGAAUUAUUUUAAAGCUUUUACAUCUUAUAUCCUAACUUCUAAAAUUCUAUGUCCAUGAUGGAAUCCUAAAGUCAUGUAAAGAAGAUUUGAUUGCCUUGGGAAAUGCACAUAAUGUAGCACUUGGUGAAAAUAUCAGGUAUCAAAACAGUAUAUAAAGUAUUUAUUUACUUAUUUAUUUAAGACAGGGUCUUGCUCUGUCAUCCAGACUGGAGUGCAGGGGCGUGAUCAUGGCUCACUGCAGCCUUAACCUCCUGGGCUCAGGUAAUCCUCCUACCUCAGCCUCCCAAGUAGCUGGGACCACAGGCACAUACCACCACAGCCAGUUGAUUUAUUUUUAUAUUUUUUUGUAGCAACAGGGAUUUGCCAUGUUGCCCAGGCUGGUCUCAAACUCCUGGGCUCAAGCAAUCUUCCCACCUCUACCUCAAAGUGCUGGGAUUACAGGCGUGAGCCACUGUGCCCAGUCAUGGUUUUUGUUUGUUUGUUUUACAAAAAGUUAUGUACAUGCAUAGAAAGAAUAUUUAUAGAAACAUUAUCUUUGGGUGGAGGAAUUACAGAUGAUUUGACAUUUUUGUCCUUGUUUUGGAUCAUUUCCAGAUUUUCCUACAAUAAGUAAGACAGAAAAAGCCCCAAACUGUGGCAUAUACAUUGAACUUUAGGAAGUGAAAUCAUAUUUUAUAUUUGUUGGGGAAAAUUUCUUUGUAAAGGAGUUCCAUGAUAAUCACUCAGUAAAGUGUGGUGGUCAUUUGCUCAUUUUAUAACUCAUGAUACAGGGCUAUAUAGGCAUGCAUUCAUUCAUCUGUUUAUCCAUGUUUUACAUUCUAUCUGCUUCCAGAAAGGAUCCCGGCAAUUCACUUGCAUGGUACCCUGAAGUGUGUAUGAUUGCCUUUCCUGUUCUAAGUGUAAAAGAGAAUAAUACCUACUUUUCAGAGAUGUUGUCAGUACUGAAGACAAUAUAUAUGGAGAAACAACAAAUGCAAUAAAUAAGAACUAUUAUUGAUUUAGAGCAAUAUCAUAAUUAGAAACAUAUUUAUGAUUUAGUGUUACUUCACAGCCAUUAAUAGGAUGUUGACUACUAUAAUAUUGAUAUGUUACAUGUUAGAAGAGAUGGAGGAAGGGGCCAUCCUGGCAAACUAGAUUAGAAGAAUAAAUCCUGGAGGUCAGUAUGGUGACCAGAUGGUUCUUACAUCUGUGUAAGAAAAUAUGAAAAAAAGGACCUGGUAGCACUUCUUACAUGGAGUGACAAUCUAACAGAAGGACUUCAUUUGCUUUUUAUUUCCAGCAUCUGGUGCAAAUCAUUUUACAUGUAUUUUCUUUGAUCCUUACUAUAACCCUAUCUAUGAGGUAGGUACUAUUAUUAACUUCAUUUCAUGUGUGAGCAAGAGGAGGUUUGGAGAAGUAAACUAACCUGUCUAAGGCCACCAGUUAGGAAAUGGCAGAGCCAGGACUUGAACCCAGGCUGACUCUAGAGCUCAUUCUUUUUUUAAAAAAAUUUUUUUUUUUUUUUGAGACAAGGUCUUGCUUUGUUACCCAGGUUGGAGUGCAGUGGUGCAAUCACAGUUCACUGCAGCCUCAACCUCCCAGGCUCAAGAAAUCCUCCCACCUCAACCUCCUGAGUAGCUAGGACUACAGGUGCGUGCCACCAUGCCAAGCUAAUUUUCUUUUAUUUUUUGUAGAGAUGGAGUCUCACUAUGUUGCCCAGGCUAGUCUCUAACUCCUGAGCUCAAGUGAUCCUCCUGCCUUGGCCUCCCGAAAGUGCAGGGUUAUAGGCAUGAGCUACCAUGCCCAGCCUAGAGCUCACCCUCUUAACCACUUCAUAGAUUGUCUGAAUCUUGGAAUAUGGGUCCAUAGAGGUCUCCUUCUAUUUGAUUUCAGGCAGCCUUGGGUUAGCUUGGAGCUCUGGGUCACUCUGAGCAUGUCUACCCAGGGUGUGCUUCAGAGUCACUAGAAAGUUGAGGGGUUUUGGGAUUAGGGAUAACGCCAGGGAAUCCUGGGCCCUACUUCCACCUUCAACCAUAAUUGAUAAAAUAGAGAGCUUUUCUCAUUUACUUAACUUCUCUUGUCCAGUUUUUGAGUAGCUAGUAACCUAUAGGAAAGUGGGUGGGACAGUCACAAAAAAAUGUGUCCUAAUGUGAUCCUAACCUCACUAUGACCUAGUGCUAUGUUGUCAUUUGCUUAGAGGGGUAUGUUGUAUAAAAUAUGAUUUAAAGAAAAACAAGAACAACCCUAAACCAGUGUGCUUUUUGCCAUGAGAAAACAGAAUUGGGUGUUUAAAAUGAGAAUGUGUUCAACGCUAGCUUCAUCUUCAGUUUCCCAGUCUCCCUUUGACACCCCCUCCGUGUGUCAUGACCUUUUCCAUGACCUUCAGGGACUGGGCCUUCUGACUUAUACAAAAGCCUCCUCUUUGGAAAGGAUUUGAACCUUGGAGAGAAUUUAAGAGAUGAGUUGCCUUUUCCUAGAGCAUUUACAUUUUAAACUUUAUGCUCACUUGUGGCAUGAGAGAUUCUGUUUCCUGCUAAAGCAAUUUCAGGCAGUAGCAAAUAGGUGGGGAAAGAGCUUUACAGGAGGAAAUCCUUUAGGGUCUCCCUGUGAUUCAUGCACACGGUCAUCUGGACCUGCUAGGGAUAAUUUUCCUCACUUGGUUAGUAAUAAUAACAACAACUACACACUUAUGAGCAGUUGUUCUGCCAGGCAUUUGUGGCCAGUGCUUGGCAGGCAGUAUCUUUUUGAACCCUCACACUCAUCUGUGAGGACAGUUUCCCUUCAUAGAUUAAGAACCCGAGGUCCAGAGAUGUUAUGCAACCUUCCUAGGGACACAGAGCUAGUAAUAGGUAGAGCUAAGAUUUGAACCCAGGUCUUUCCAGCGCCAGACCCUGAAUUUGUAGGAUUAGUGCCUUCAGGAUGACAUGGAGGGACCUCACUGCCUUGAUCUGUUAUUUAUCAAGAGUCAAACUGGAAAAGGCUGUCAGGGAAACCUCCAGGCUGCAUCUUGGGCAAAGAUUGGCUUGAAACAGGCAUUUCCCAAGCCUGGCCUUGGACACCAACUGUAAAAAAAAGGCCAUUACUGGUGUUUCCUUGGUUAGUUCUGGGUAUAAGUUCUGGAUCCUCACUCAUCUCAUCUGCACUGACAUCCUCACUCACGGCAUUUAGAGACUUAACACGCCAGCCUCUGUGUGAGCAUUUACCUCUUUCAACCCUCACCAUAAUCCCACAAGGAGGCACAGUUCUUUUACCCAUUUUGAAGAUGAAGAAACACAGUCUCAGAGAAGUUCGGUCACAGUAUCACAAGGAGGUAAGUAGCAGAGCUGGGAUUGGAGCCCCGGCCUUUGUGAUCCCAGAGCACCAGCAAUACCGUCUCGGCCUCGGCUCCUGGGUUAUACCCUCUGUCACGCCAAGCCCAUCAGCCCGCUUGUGCUGUCUCCCUCUGUCUGUCCUAGUUCGGAUGGAGAUGGCGAGUUCUGCUGGCUCCUGGCUCUCUGGCUGCCUCAUCCCUCUCGUCUUCCUCCGGCUGUCUGUGCAUGUGUCAGGCCACGCAGGGGAUGCCGGCAAGUUCCACGUGGCCCUACUAGGGGGCACAGCCGAGCUGCUCUGCCCUCUCUCCCUCUGGCCCGGGACGGUACCCAAGGAGGUGAGGUGGCUGCGGUCCCCAUUCCCGCAGCGCUCCCAGGCUGUUCACAUAUUCCGGGAUGGGAAGGACCAGGAUGAAGAUCUGAUGCCGGAAUAUAAGGGGAGGACGGUGCUAGUGAGAGAUGCCCAAGAGGGAAGUGUCACUCUGCAGAUCCUUGACGUGCGCCUUGAGGACCAAGGGUCUUACCGAUGUCUGAUCCAAGUUGGAAAUCUGAGUAAAGAGGACACCGUGAUCCUGCAGGUUGCAGCCCCAUCUGUGGGGAGUCUCUCCCCCUCAGCAGUGGCUCUGGCUGUGAUCCUGCCUGUCCUGGUACUUCUCAUCAUGGUGUGCCUUUGCCUUAUCUGGAAGCAAAGAAGAGCAAAAGAAAAGCUUCUCUAUGAACAUGUGACGGAGGUGGACAAUCUUCUUUCAGACCAUGCUAAAGAAAAAGGAAAACUCCAUAAAGCUGUCAAGAAACUCCGGAGUGAACUGAAGUUGAAAAGAGCUGCAGCAAACUCAGGCUGGAGAAGAGCCCGGUUGCAUUUUGUGGCAGUGACCCUGGACCCAGACACAGCACAUCCCAAACUCAUCCUUUCUGAGGACCAAAGAUGUGUAAGGCUUGGAGACAGACGGCAGCCUGUACCUGACAACCCCCAGAGAUUUGAUUUCGUUGUCAGCAUCCUAGGCUCUGAGUACUUCACGACUGGCUGCCACUACUGGGAGGUGUAUGUGGGAGACAAGACCAAAUGGAUUCUUGGAGUAUGUAGUGAGUCAGUGAGCAGGAAGGGGAAGGUUACUGCCUCACCUGCCAAUGGACACUGGCUUCUGCGACAGAGUCGUGGGAAUGAGUAUGAAGCUCUCACAUCCCCGCAGACCUCCUUCCGCCUUAAAGAGCCUCCACGGUGUGUGGGGAUUUUCCUGGACUAUGAAGCAGGAGUCAUCUCUUUCUACAAUGUGACCAACAAGUCCCACAUCUUUACUUUCACCCACAAUUUCUCUGGCCCCCUUCGCCCUUUCUUUGAACCUUGCCUUCAUGAUGGAGGAAAAAACACAGCACCUCUAGUCAUUUGUUCAGAACUACACAAAUCAGAGGAAUCAAUUGUCCCCAGGCCAGAAGGGAAAGGCCAUGCUAAUGGAGAUGUGUCCCUCAAGGUGAACUCUUCUUUACUACCCCCGAAGGCCCCAGAGCUGAAGGAUAUAAUCCUGUCCUUGCCCCCUGACCUUGGCCCAGCCCUUCAGGAGCUCAAGGCUCCUUCUUUUUAGGGAUAUGCCACAUUACCUGCUCCCAUCACCAUCCAGCCCAGCACCCUGGACUUCAGUCGCCUGGCCCAACCCCAUGAUUAUGGAACGUCUCUUCACCUUAACCCAAAUCCAGACCCUUUUGUGGUUUCUAUUUGUACCACUUUUCUCCCAGGCCUCAGUUCUGAAGCUUACCUUUCUUCUAAGGAAUUGAAGCUCCCAGUGACCUGGAGGGAGGAUUCCUGGAAACCAAACAAUCAGUUUAGGUGCAGGUGGAGAUGUUGAAUAUGUGUUACCAAGAUACAGCACAGGUUCAGGGAAAAGAGUUCGCUACUCCAGGGGUUAUUUAGAAGACACUUUCUCUGCCUCAUCCUGCCCUCAAGCUUUAGUCAAGAAGUUAUGGCCCCCAGUCCCUGACUUCUUACUUAUCCCAUUGAGGACUGCCUUUCUCUCUCUCAGUUCUGGCCUCUGCCCCCCAAAGUCAGCUCUCUAAAAGCAAGCAUGUUUUAGACCACUCACUCUUUCCCUCUUUCUUCAGGAAUGAAUUGGGAAAGGCUGAUGAGUAAAACAUACCAUCCUUUUCUAUUUUCUUGAUGCUGUUUACAACAUAGUUUGGUGAUAUCCAGAGCUAAUGUACAUGCUUUCAAAAGCUAAUCUGCCUGUUGAUGGUAACUAGGUACAGCGACUUUAAAUACAGUUGCUAUAAUCCUGAAAAGCCCCAGGAGCACAUCAGGGAGCUGGGAAACACAGUUGCAGAGAACUCAGCUGUAUGUUGCCCUCUGACCUUGGCCCAGACCUUCAGAGGCUCAGUCUGUUGAGUCUGUUGUGACUGUCUUAUGAAUCAAUCUGUUGUGCCAACCCUUUCUGAGAUUCAGAGAGGUCCAGCUAGAAAAAGUGGCAGUUUUAACCACCAACGUAGAAGCUUUUUUUUCCCCACAAGACCAUUGUACUGCAAUACUUGAGUAUUUGUGUAGCAAACAGCCUCUUAGGUUGGAGAGUAUUGAUUUCAAAUAGGAAGUUGGUAGACUAGGUGUGAGGAUGAAAUAAUGACCUUGAUUUUUGGGUGUGUAUUGCAGAAGCCUCGUCGCUUUCAAGUCACAUCAUAUAUGCGAUCUGGCCUAACCAUGGAGAUAUUGGUUAUCAGUUUGCAGAUGAAUACACAGUUCUAUCCAACAGAAACUGUAUCUUUCUGUUUGUCAGAAGUUCUCCGUUAGUUCCUGUAUUAGUCAAGGUUUUCCAGAGAAACAGAAUCAAUAUAUAUUGGGGCAGGGGGGCGGUGGUUAUUAUAAGGAAUUGGCUCACGUGAUUAUGGAGGCGGUUAAAUCCCAAGAUCUGCAGGAUAAGUCAGCAAGAUGGAGUCCCAUGAGAGCUGAUGGUUUAGUUCCAGUCUGAUGGCAGCAGGCUUGACGCCAAGGAAGAGAUGAUGUUUAAUUCAAGUCCGAAGGCAAGGAAAAAGCUGAUGGUCCUGUCCAAAGGCUAUUAGGCAGGAAGAAUUCUCUUAGGGCAGAGUUAGCUCUUUUGUUCUAUUCAGGCCUUCAACUGAUUCAGCAAGGCCCGCCCACAUUUGGGAGGACAGUCUGCAUUACUCAGUCUACUGAUUUGAAUGUUAAUGUCAUUGAGAAACACCCUCACAGGAACACUCAGAAUAAUGUUUGACCAAAUAGCUGGGCAUCUUGUGACCCAGUUAAGUGGAUACAUAAGAUUAACUAUCACAGUGACUCAGUGGAAUUUUUUGUUUGCUUUUGUACAGUUUUAAAAUAAAAGUUUGGUAUUUGUGUUUUGG